AUAACAGACCAUCUGUAGACUCCUUCGGAAAGCAGCAGAGACGCUGCAGAGGGCUUUUCUUAGACAUCAACUGCAGACGGCUGGCAGGAUAGAAGCAGCGGCUCACUUGGACUUUUUCACCAGGGAAAUCAGAGACAAUGAUGGGGCUCUUCCCCAGAACUACAGGGGCUCUGGCCAUCUUCGUGGUGGUCAUAUUGGUUCAUGGAGAAUUGCGAAUAGAGACUAAAGGUCAAUAUGAUGAAGAAGAGAUGACUAUGCAACAAGCUAAAAGAAGGCAAAAACGUGAAUGGGUGAAAUUUGCCAAACCCUGCAGAGAAGGAGAAGAUAACUCAAAAAGAAACCCAAUUGCCAAGAUUACUUCAGAUUACCAAGCAACCCAGAAAAUCACCUACCGAAUCUCUGGAGUGGGAAUCGAUCAGCCGCCUUUUGGAAUCUUUGUUGUUGACAAAAACACUGGAGAUAUUAACAUAACAGCUAUAGUCGACCGGGAGGAAACUCCAAGCUUCCUGAUCACAUGUCGGGCUCUAAAUGCCCAAGGACUAGAUGUAGAGAAACCACUUAUACUAACGGUUAAAAUUUUGGAUAUUAAUGAUAAUCCUCCAGUAUUUUCACAACAAAUUUUCAUGGGUGAAAUUGAAGAAAAUAGUGCCUCAAACUCACUGGUGAUGAUACUAAAUGCCACAGAUGCAGAUGAACCAAACCACUUGAAUUCUAAAAUUGCCUUCAAAAUUGUCUCUCAGGAACCAGCAGGCACACCCAUGUUCCUCCUAAGCAGAAACACUGGGGAAGUCCGUACUUUGACCAAUUCUCUUGACCGAGAGCAAGCUAGCAGCUAUCGUCUGGUUGUGAGUGGUGCAGACAAAGAUGGAGAAGGACUAUCAACUCAAUGUGAAUGUAAUAUUAAAGUGAAAGAUGUCAACGAUAACUUCCCAAUGUUUAGAGACUCUCAGUAUUCAGCACGUAUUGAAGAAAAUAUUUUAAGUUCUGAAUUACUUCGAUUUCAAGUAACAGAUUUGGAUGAAGAGUACACAGAUAAUUGGCUUGCAGUAUAUUUCUUUACCUCUGGGAAUGAAGGAAAUUGGUUUGAAAUACAAACUGAUCCUAGAACUAAUGAAGGCAUCCUGAAAGUGGUGAAGGCUCUAGAUUAUGAACAACUACAAAGCGUGAAACUUAGUAUUGCUGUCAAAAACAAAGCUGAAUUUCACCAAUCAGUUAUCUCUCGAUACCGAGUUCAGUCAACCCCAGUCACAAUUCAGGUAAUAAAUGUAAGAGAAGGAAUUGCAUUCCGUCCUGCUUCCAAGACAUUUACUGUGCAAAAAGGCAUAAGUAGCAAAAAAUUGGUGGAUUAUAUCCUGGGAACAUAUCAAGCCAUCGAUGAGGACACUAACAAAGCUGCCUCAAAUGUCAAAUAUGUCAUGGGACGUAACGAUGGUGGAUACCUAAUGAUUGAUUCAAAAACUGCUGAAAUCAAAUUUGUCAAAAAUAUGAACCGAGAUUCUACUUUCAUAGUUAACAAAACAAUCACAGCUGAGGUUCUGGCCAUAGAUGAAUACACGGGUAAAACUUCUACAGGCACGGUAUAUGUUAGAGUACCCGAUUUCAAUGACAAUUGUCCAACAGCUGUCCUCGAAAAAGAUGCAGUUUGCAGUUCUUCACCUUCCGUGGUUGUCUCCGCUAGAACACUGAAUAAUAGAUACACUGGCCCCUAUACAUUUGCACUGGAAGAUCAACCUGUAAAGUUGCCUGCCGUAUGGAGUAUCACAACCCUCAAUGCUACCUCGGCCCUCCUCAGAGCCCAGGAACAGAUACCUCCUGGAGUAUACCACAUCUCCCUGGUACUUACAGACAGUCAGAACAAUCGGUGUGAGAUGCCACGCAGCUUGACACUGGAAGUCUGUCAGUGUGACAACAGGGGCAUCUGUGGAACUUCUUACCCAACCACAAGCCCUGGGACCAGGUAUGGCAGGCCGCACUCAGGGAGGCUGGGGCCUGCCGCCAUCGGCCUGCUGCUCCUUGGUCUCCUGCUGCUGCUGUUGGCCCCCCUUCUGCUGUUGACCUGUGACUGUGGGGCAGGUUCUACUGGGGGAGUGACAGGUGGUUUUAUCCCAGUUCCUGAUGGCUCAGAAGGAACAAUUCAUCAGUGGGGAAUUGAAGGAGCCCAUCCUGAAGACAAGGAAAUCACAAAUAUUUGUGUGCCUCCUGUAACAGCCAAUGGAGCCGAUUUCAUGGAAAGUUCUGAAGUUUGUACAAAUACGUAUGCCAGAGGCACAGCGGUGGAAGGCACUUCAGGAAUGGAAAUGACCACUAAGCUUGGAGCAGCCACUGAAUCUGGAGGUGCUGCAGGCUUUGCAACAGGGACAGUGUCAGGAGCUGCUUCAGGAUUCGGAGCAGCCACUGGAGUUGGCAUCUGUUCCUCAGGGCAGUCUGGAACCAUGAGAACAAGGCAUUCCACUGGAGGAACCAAUAAGGACUACGCUGAUGGGGCGAUAAGCAUGAAUUUUCUGGACUCCUACUUUUCUCAGAAAGCAUUUGCCUGUGCGGAGGAAGACGAUGGCCAGGAAGCAAAUGACUGCUUGUUGAUCUAUGAUAAUGAAGGCGCAGAUGCCACUGGUUCUCCUGUGGGCUCCGUGGGUUGUUGCAGUUUUAUUGCUGAUGACCUGGAUGACAGCUUCUUGGACUCACUUGGACCCAAAUUUAAAAAACUUGCAGAGAUAAGCCUUGGUGUUGAUGGUGAAGGCAAAGAAGUUCAGCCACCCUCUAAAGACAGCGGUUAUGGGAUUGAAUCCUGUGGCCAUCCCAUAGAAGUCCAGCAGACAGGAUUUGUUAAGUGCCAGACUUUGUCAGGAAGUCAAGGAGCUUCUGCUUUGUCCACCUCUGGGUCUGUCCAGCCAGCUGUUUCCAUCCCUGACCCUCUGCAGCAUGGUAACUAUUUAGUAACGGAGACUUACUCGGCUUCUGGUUCCCUCGUGCAACCUUCCACUGCAGGCUUUGAUCCACUUCUCACACAAAAUGUGAUAGUGACAGAAAGGGUGAUCUGUCCCAUUUCCAGUGUUCCUGGCAACCUAGCUGGCCCAACGCAGCUACGAGGGUCACAUACUAUGCUCUGUACAGAGGAUCCUUGCUCCCGUCUAAUAUGACCAGAAUGAGCUGGAAUACCACACUGACCAAAUCUGGAUCUUUGGACUAAAGUAUUCAAAAUAGCAUAGCAAAGCUCACUGUAUUGGGCUAAUAAUUUGGCACUUAUUAGCUUCUCUCAUAAACUGAUCACGAUUAUAAAUUAAAUGUUUGGGUUCAUACCCCAAAAGCAAUAUGUUGUCACUCCUAAUUCUCAAGUACUAUUCAAAUUGUAGUAAAUCUUAAAGUUUUUCAAAACCCUAAAAUCAUAUUCGCCAGGAAAUUUUCCUAAACAUUCUUAAGCUUCUAUUUUUCCCCUGCCAAAGGAAGGUGUUUAUCAUUUUAAAAUGCAAUGUGAUUUAGUGGAUUAAGCAGGAGCGCUGGUUCUUGUCUCCAUUGCCUUUUCUUAUAUCAUUGAUAAUGAUGUAAGAAUCACAAGGGGCCGGGCGCGGUGGCUCACGCCUGUAAUCCCAGCACUUUGGGAGGCCGAGGCAGGUGGAUCAUGAGGUCAGGAGAUCGAGACCAUCCUGGCUAACAAGGUGAAACCCCGUCUCUACUAAAAAUACAAAAAAUUAGCCGGGCGCAGUGGCGGGCGCCUGUAGUCCCAGCUACUCGGGAGGCUGAGGCAGGAGAAUGGCAUGAACCCGGGAAGCGGAGCUUGCAGUGAGCCGAGAUUGCGCCACUGCAGUCCGCAGUCCGGCCUGGGCGACAGAGCGAGACUCCGUCUCAAAAAAAAAAAAAAAAAAAGAAUCACAAGGUAUUUGCUAAAGCAUUUUGAGCUGCUUGGAAAAAGGGAAGUAGUUGCAGUAGAGUUUCUUCCAUCUUCUUGGUGCUGGGAAGCCAUAUAUGUGUCUUUUACUCAAGCUAAGGGGUAUAAGCUUAUGUGUUGAAUUUGCUACAUCUAUAUUUCACAUAUUCUCACAAUAAGAGAAUUUUGAAAUAGAAAUAUCAUAGAACAUUUAAGAAAGUUUAGUAUAAAUAAUAUUUUGUGUGUUUUAAUCCCUUUGAAGGGAUCUAUCCAAAGAAAAUAUUUUACACUGAGCUCCUUCCUACACGUCUCAGUAACAGAUCCUGUGUUAGUCUUUGAAAAUAGCUCAUUUUUUAAAUGUCAGUGAGUAGAUGUAGCAUACAUAUGAUGUAUAAUGACGUGUAUUAUGUUAACAAUGUCUGCAGAUUUUGUAGGAAUACAAAACAUGGCCUUUUUUAUAAGCAAAACGGGCCAAUGACUAGAAUAACACAUAGGGCAAUCUGUGAAUAUGUAUUAUAAGCAGCAUUCCAGAAAAGUAGUUGGUGAAAUAAUUUUCAAGUCAAAAAGGGAUAUGGAAAGGGAAUUAUGAGUAACCUCUAUUUUUUAAGCCUUGCUUUUAAAUUAAACAGCUACAGCCAUUUAAGCCUUGAGGAUAAUAAAGCUUGAGAGUAAUAAUGUUAGGUUAGCAAAGGUUUAGAUGUAUCACUUCAUGCAUGCUACCAUGAUAGUAAUGCAGCUCUUCGAGUCAUUUCUGGUCAUUCAAGAUAUUCACCCUUUUGCCCAUAGAAAGCACCCUACCUCACCUGCUUACUGACAUUGUCUUAGCUGAUCACAAGAUCAUUAUCAGCCUCCAUUAUUCCUUACUGUAUAUAAAAUACAGAGUUUUAUAUUUUCCUUUCUUCGUUUUUCACCAUAUUCAAAACCUAAAUUUGUUUUUGCAGAUGGAAUGCAAAGUAAUCAAGUGUUUGUGCUUUCACCUAGAAGGGUGUGGUCCUGAAGGAAAGAGGUCCCCUAAAUAUCCCCCACCCUGGUGCUCCUCCCUCUCCCUGGUACCCUGACUACCAGGAAGUCAGGUGCUAGAGCAGCUGGAGAAGUGCAGGCAGCCUGUGCUUCCACAGAUGGGGGUGCUGCUGCAACAAGGCUUUCAAUGUGCCCAUCUUAGGUGGGAGAAGCUAGAUCCUGUGCAGCAGCCUGGUAAGUCCUGAGGAGGUUCCAUUGCUCUUCCUGCUGCUGUCCUUUGCUUCUCAACGGUGGCUCGCUCUACAGUCUAGAGCACAUGCAGCUAACUUGUGCCUCUGCUUAUGCAUGAGGGUUAAAUUAACAACCAUAACCUUCAUUUGAAGUUCAAAGGUGUAUUCAGGAUCCUCAAAGCAUUUUAACCUUGCCGCUUAAAACCCAAUUUACCGUGAAAUGGGAAUUUUGCUGCAUUGUUAAACUGUAGUGGAAACCAUGCUAUAGUAAUAAAGGUUAUAUAAGAGAGAAAUUGAAAUUAAAUGUGUUUUUAAAUUUCAAAAAAAAAUCAAUCUUUAGGAUGACUUAAAAAUUGAUUUGCCAUGUAAAAUGUAUCUGCAUUUUUUACACAAAACUUGUUUUAAGCAUAAAAUUUUAAAACUGUACUACUUGAUGUAUUAUACAUUUUGAACCAUAUGUAUUAAACCAUAAACAGUAUAAUGUUGUUAUAAUAAAACAGGCAAUAAAUUUAUAAAUAAAAGCUGAA